UAGAGACAAAGUUUUGCCGUGUUGCCCAGGCUCAUGCUACCUCUUUUAACCAUAGCCUUAAGUGAUGCCCCACCCUGAACCAUACUCAGGACUGAUUAAAAAUAAUCACCCCAUGAAUGAGUGACAAGAAGAUGCUACAGUCUCAUUUACCAGCUCUAUGAAAUCAGGCAAGUUGCUUUACCUCUCUUAAGUCCCAUUUUCCUGAUCUGUCAAAGGGGGAUGAACAUACCUGCCUUAUAGAGUAGUUUCGAGAACUAAAUGAAGUAAUAGUGAGAUAAUAGGAUAUAAUGUGCCCAGUACAAUGGCUGGUAUCUAAUAAACACAUUCUAGUUCUUUAUAAUAAAUAUAUUACUAUUAUUACUAUCAUUUGUAGUUUUUAUAAUGAAGAAAUCAGUGAUGGGGGGCAACUCUGAACUGGCAAUUAGAAAAUUCUUGAUACAUUAUUUUAAAGUGAAAAAAAAAAUACCAUAAAAAGCAAGCUUUCAUGGCUGCUGUGGGGUAGCUAGUGUGAGAUAAUUUAAUUUUUUUCUUUAUAAACCAAUCAAUAGGUAAAAAAGCCUAUAACCAUUCUUCCACUUGGAGGCAAUAUCCUCUUCUGAUGGAGACAGUUUCUCUGGACGGAAGCCACCCAACCACAGAUCAGCCUGUUUGUCCACACCUGCGUCUAGUCAAAGGCAGAAUCUCUAUACAGUGGCCAGACUAAAGAGUCAGAUUAACAGGAUGUAAGUCAAGCAAUGGCUUACCUUCCCAGCCACAGCAAAUGAGGGAAACAGUGUUCUAGGAUGACUUAAUCUAUUAUGGCAUUAAAAUGCUAUAUCCAGAUCUAAAGCUAGAAACCAAAUCUCCAAAGAGGAAAAGACAUCCUAUAACCAAAGCAACUUAUACAUAGUUAUAGAGGAACUCUAUUGUCAUCAGUUGCUUGAUGGAAAAGAAGAGAAACCCAUGUGUGUAGGUUUUUUUUCCCCCAAAGUCCAAAUUAGACCCAUUUGGAGGAAUGGCAUUGGGGAAAAUAGCAAGGCUCAGGCAAAAGGAAUUGGGUAUACCAAGAGAAAUACGAUGUUCAGAGUAAGAAAGAUAAUAGUUCUACGACAUUCUGAAAAUGUUCACUUCUGAGGGCUCUAUUGAAAGAGAAAUGUUGACAAACUGGAAUCAAUUUAGAAAGAAUGCUGAAAAAGGUGAGAGUCUGGAGCUCAUGUCCUUUAUAUGGGCAUGUGUCUAAUGCCUAAUACCUAGUAGAUGUUCAGUUAGUGCUUGUGGAAAGUAGGAAAGGUCAGUCCACAUAGUAAAGCAGAGAAAGGCAGGGAGGGAGGGAGAGGAGAACGGGAUAAGUUGAAUUUCCUUAUCUUAGGCUGCUUGCCUAAGAAAGGUGAAAGCAGGGGGUGAAUUAAUACCUCUAAUCAAAUAUCUGAAGGGCUCUCGUGUGGAAGAAAAAUAAUACUAGUUUUGUGUAACUCCAGAGGAAAGAAUUAGGAUUUAUGGGUAACAGUUGAAUGGGGAAAGAUUUUUAGCACAAAAUAAAGUAGGACUUUCUAAAAACAAGAAACAUUUUUAAAAUGGAAUGUGCUACCUUACAGAGUAGUAAGAAGUCUUUCCAGUAAGGUGGGUAAAUUUCUAUCAGAAUUAUUGUAGAAACCAAUUAUUUCCGGCUUUGGGUGGAGAGUUAAAAAGUCCAUGACUCUCCCAUAUGACGAGAGCCAAUAAGCUGCUCCUACUCAUCUGAGGUUUAAAAAAAGUCACUUGUUUCUGAGCUCAUUUCUGUUCCUAACAAAGACUCUGGACCAUGCAGAGCUCAUUCUUGAGCCUUUACAAUGCUGUGUGAUGGGAAGUGAAUUUCUAUAGUAAAAAUCGAUGUUGAUUUAUACUAUACUUUUAAAGUUAUUUUUCAUAAAACAUAGACAGUAAGCUUAAGAAGUGAGAAGCAUUUACACCAAAACUUUUAAAAUAUUAUUUUAUCUAAAGAUAUAAAUCUCUUGUUGGUCAAAGGAUACAAAAUUUCCAUUAGACAGGAGGUUCAAGAGAUAUAUCGAAAAACAUGGUGAUUACAGUUAAGUGUUCUCACUACAAAAAAAUGAUAAGGAUGUGAGGUAAUGGAUGUGUUAAUUAGCUUGAUUUCACCAUUCCACACUGUAUGCAUAUUUCACAUCAUAUGCACCAUAAAUAAAUACAAUUUUUGUCAAUUAAAUAUUUUAAAAGAAAUCUCUAUGUAAGGAUAGUUAAUCUAUUAGAUAUAAAUAAUACUCCAUAUAGCUAUGUAAGGUUGAUAUGAAGAAAUCAAGCUAUGAUCCACAGACGGCAAUAAAUCCUGUUAUUCUAUUCCAUAUGCUGCAUACAUAUAAAGCUAGAGAGGCCUUUUAGUACGAGGUAAGAGUGUGGACAAAGACAAAUGGAAAAAGACAAAUGACAAAAGUGCUAAAAACAGCUUCAGUUUCCCUGCAACUCCUAGUUAGUCGAGUGAAACAAAGGAGGCUCUCUAAGAAUCAGUUUCUUGGUGGCUGUCCUGGAUGUCCGUAGUACAACACUUCACUCCCAUGUCCAGGAUUAACGUGCAACAGUCUGCUUGCCUCUCCUGUUAUAGCCCAGAAGGAUCACAAAAGGAUUUCCUGCCACAUGCUGCCCACCUGUAUCUUGGCAGCCUAGCACAGCCCGACCCAAACGGCACUACUACUUGCUGGUUACAGGAGCCAUUUGCAUUUUCAACCAUGGCUAUUUUAAGGCUAUGCAAAUGAGUUGGCGGGACUUUCUCCUUUAAAAGACAAUGAAAAAAAUUCAUAGUCUAACAUCUCCUUCUUUAACUUUUCUAAUACAUCUAAACCCAAUACACACUUAUUUUUAUGGAAUCAGAGCAGGAUACUUUAAGUCUUCUCUGGAGACUAAUUUUGGCUGCCCUUUGAGGAACAGUUAGAACCACUCAUCAGGCUGCUAGCACUAGCAAAGGGGAAGCCACGCUGUCAUAACUGGCUCUUGCAGUCGCUGCUUCCACUUCACCAUCCUGAAAGCUUGAUGGCUUAUCUGCUUAGGAAACUCAGGAAUGUUUCUCACCACCCCACUUCGCUACCCAGAGCCACUACCCAUUAGAGUUACCGAACUGACCCUUUUUCUUUUAAAGGUUGGAAGCAAAAAGACUAUAAAUCUUUUACAGCUGCAUUCAUUACAGCAGUUAACAUUCUCUAUAAUGAUACAGUUCUAAAAAGCAUUAUCUAAAAAGAAAAAUUAUUUUUGAGAGCUGAGAGGCUAAAACUGGGUGAAGACUUCUGCAGAGAAAAUAUUUUUAAAGUCAUAAAACCAUGAAAAUAACAACUACUGUACGUUUUAUUUUAUAGAAAUCAAGUAGUAUCUAAUAGACAAGGGAAGACAUUGAUCCAUAAACUUUUUAAAGAAAAUUUGGUAAUCUCUUAAAGUAUUUGUAUGGCUUUGAAUGGGUGUGCUUUUCUAACUUUGUUUUAAUUUUUAUGAUACACUUAUAAUUGUUUCAAAUAGGCAUUUGUUCAUUUUAAAACUACUAGAAGUUACACUGAAGAAAAGCAUUCAAAAGAAGACUUUUGAACAAAAAAAUUGUUGAAUGAGUGAAAUGCCUGAAGUAGCUCAAUUUACCAAACAGAAAUCACUCAGUAUUACAAGCCUGCAGAUUUCAGUUUUACUGAUUUCAGUUCUGUCUGCCCAGUUCAUUUCCAAAUUUGUAUCAGUUUUACAUACUUUAGACAUUGGCGCCAUAUAUGAAGCUAAAAAAAUUAGCAUACUUGUUUAUUUUGUUUAUAUUCUUAUUUUUAGUAGUGGUUUCAAAAUUCUUAUAUAGGCAAAGAAUGGGCUGGCUGUCAGGGUUGGCAGCGUGGAUGGAGAGUGGGAACCCGAGGGGAGGGCUUGAAUCUGCUAUUACUUAGCCUUUUAAAGAAAACUGAGGAAAUAUGAUUUUUCUCUUCAAGGAAUGGUGUUAGAGGUCAGUGGCUGCUAGAAUUUAUGAGAUUACGCCGUUGCCCCUACAAAAACAUUGCUUUGUGCUACCAUUGCACACUGCGAAUUCUGCGAAGUUUAACAAGGCCACUGAAAUCUUUAGUUUCCAAGGUUGUGUGUUGGGCGGUAAUCUAUCCCUUCUCUCUGAGUUUCCUGAAAUACAGAUGCAGAAGAAAGUUUCAGAAAGAAACAGUUUCUCUCAAAUGUAUACAUGGGAAAUCCAAACAAAUUUGUCCGUUGAGGUUAGGAACAAACUCAACAUACCUUUCCUCCAGUUAACCAACCUGCUUUCCAAAAAAGCCAAUUUAGGUUAAGGUUACUUUUGAGAAAUUUGUACUUUUUGUUUCAGAAUCUGUAAUAAUUUCAUGUUUGCUGAUUGCUGAUAUUUGGUCAACAAUACUAUAGAGCCAGUUCUUACUUUUUGUAUGAAUUGGCACUCUGCCUACUGGCUUCAAGAAUGUAGAAGAAAGCAGGAGAGGAAAGAAUAGGAAUGAUGGGAGAAUAAAGAGACUCAUUAUCAUUGUCUCUUUAAAACUGAGAGCUAGAAGGGGCCUUGGAGAUGAUUUUAUUCAGUAAUACUAAGUACUUAGAGAAUACAUGUACAUAGUUUUGUCCUGUAAUACAAAAAAUAGUGGUGUCUAGGGACCUAAUAAUAGGAAUAUUAAAAUGAUUAUAUUUACUUAAGGAACAUUUCAUAUUAUAAGGUACUAUUGGCCAUUGGAUAUAAAUGAUUUAUCAAUAAGAAAAAGGAUAGUAGUAUUUCAUAAAAGUGUUCAUUUAGCAGGAUUCAAAACAAUAUCCAAGAAGAACCUGGAGAGAAGAUUGUGUGUGACACAAUGCCAAUUUUAAAAUGGGGGCCAGAGGCUUACAUUUACAUAAUUUUCUUUAUUUUGACUCAAUCAUUUUGGCAAAGCCACUGGCUUAGCCACACAUGAUGUAUAGCUUGUAAUAAAUAACUUUGUCUUUUGCCUCUCGUCAUCUGUAAAAUAGAUAAUACUCUUCACCUCUUUCUUCCCUCCCUCCAUAGAGUUGUCUGUCUUUAUUCAUCAGCUCUAUAUUUGGAGACUAUGUUGGGCUGAUGAUUGAACAGUGAUGAAUGAAUUAAGGUGAAUUACAAGGAUAUCCUAGAAGAUGCUUAAACUAACAUGAAAUUCAAUUAUCUAAAGUUAGUUUGUAAUACUCUAACCAUCAUAGAGGCCAAGUAUAGUGUUUCACCAAUUUUUUUGCUCACGUAGCUCAGGCCGCAUUUUUCUUUUUAGUGAUUUAUUUUCCUCCUAAUGGUACUCAAUUUGAUUUGACAUUAUUCAGAUUUAAAUGCUGAGGGAGAGGUAUGAUUUUCCUUUACCUCCUAGAAAAGAGGAUGCAGUCAAGGGCAGCUCACCGUCACUUUGAUGGUAAUGUCCUGCCAAACAAAACAGCGCGUGCUGAAGAUUUCAUUCAGCAGGCAUGGAACCCGAAUUGCUCAAUAAAUCCCCAUAUUGGUUGGUUUUAUAGCUUAAAAGAAGGAAAAUAUAAAAUAGUCUGUCCGGAUGACUCACAGAUUGUCUCUUGCUCAGUAUUAACAGUAAAAUAAUAAUCCUUUUGAUUACCAUAAAUAUAUCAAAAUACUGUAGCUAUUUUCAAAAUAUAUAGAAAUACAUAGAAAUAAUUUAGAUGUGAUUGUUGCCUAAAAAGUUAGAAAUAAAAUUUGGCCCAUAUUUUUUCCAAGAAGUCAUUAAAAGCUUUCCUUUGUUUUCAUAUUCAAAAGGAUACCACUUGUACAUGCAGAAUAGCCAACCUGCUUCCCCUCUGGUCAGUACUUGAUAACCAGAGCACACACAGACAGAAUCUCCUUUCAUUGCUGCUCUUAAUUGUGAAAGAGUUUUAUUCUUCCCCAUGUUCCCAAAUCCAGAAACUGGUACAGUUCCAAGGUGUCCUGAAUACAGAUAUCUGGCUUUGGAUGAAAUCUCCAAGGAGUUUUAUAUUCACUCACCACUUCCUGUGGAAGAAGUAGUUGUAAUAAUCAUUACAAAUAUCUUGAACUGCAAACUUAGCAGCAUUGUUUUCUUUUCUGUUUCAGACAUAUUCAGCAUUGAAUCACUGAAUAAUUUUAUUUCUAAUUAUGAAAUUGAAGCUUUGGCAGAUUUCAUUUUAUUCACUUGAAAUUAAAGCAAGUUAUUUUAUAUAUUCUAAUGAGAUCAGAAUGUUACAAGUAUGUGUUUGGAUUUUAUUUCCAUACUCUUGGAGAGAAGGCCAUAACUUGAAAAAUGACUGGAAAGAAACUAUUAUAGUCAUUAUUAAGAAGAGACUAUUUAUGAUAGUCAUUAUUUAGUAAAGUGAGUUUCCUUAAACUUGGUACAUUUCUGUGUAACCAGUGAAUUAAUUCACAAGUCAUUUAAGCUUCGUGAAUAUAUUUUAAAUGUUUAAAAUCUAUUUCAGAAGCUUAACCAAUAAGAUAAAGUUAUAUCUGAUAACCAAGCACCAUUCUGUGCACCAGUGAUACACAGCUGAGUGGCAAACUCAAAAUUUUUUGUGUGUAUAUAAUUUAUGUUUCACCAGUUCUUUCCCCAGCUCCUCACAAAUUCCCUGUACCUGUUCUUCACCAUUGACGUACACACAUACCCAUACCCAGAGAGUUUUUUCAAGAGUUCUCCCGGGAUUGAUUGUGAGUGAUUCUGGUCUGUCUUUUUCACGCCAUCUGUGGGGUAGUCCUCUUCUCUUGCUCAGGCCCCUCUCUGCUGGGUAAGACCCCCAUAUCCACUGACCACCCAGCCCUGCAUGUGUGGAGUGCCGGCUGCCUGCUGAGCGCAGUACUUGGCAGUGCUCACUGCCGUUCAUACCAGGUGUCCCAGACUCUGCUGGACACCGAUUCUUGUCUAGCUGGACACAACUUCUGACACAGGAGGCUUGCAGGUAACACACUCCACGCAGCAUUCUGUGGAAACGUUGAGGAGAAUACCUUUCUCCUCUUUUCUGUUCUGGUAGAGAGAUCACAAGCACUGCAAGGGCACCCCCAGUGUCUUAUAUGAGUACAUCCUAUUCUUUUUCAUCACGGCCUCUCUCUCCCUGGGACCCCUGGGGAAUGGAGCCAUGAAGAAUCCCAAGCGACAGACCCCCUAUUACACUUAACAUUACUUUACUCCUCUCAUGUUCAGUUAGUGCUUUGUUACUGAGGCAGCCCUGUCAGCAUCUGACACUCCACCAACGCACCUCCUUAGGAUGAGCUCCCUCUCAAGCGUAGCUCAGGUUCUCGCACAAAGGGGACUGUCCUGCCAGUUUGCAGAGGAUUCUGAAGCCAAAAGGUGAGCCAGCAGCACCAGCCACCGUGUGCAGAUGAAACAGAUGAACGAAUGCACACAAGCCCUAUAACACACUAGAAAACUGCUGUUUAAAAGAUAUUAAUGAUAUUAAUAAUUUUUAAACCUUGGUAUUUACCUCUUAAAAGUCUAAAAUAAAAAGGUUUUCGGUUUUACUAGUUGGUUUCUCCUGAGUCAUGGUGUGUAUAUUUUUAGUAUUACUGCUGCCUCAAUAUCUCUCUGCUUUAAAAUAGUGAUACUUUCCCAAAGCUUUCUCCUUGUCUCUGUUCUCUCUUCCUACUCUCCUACACUCUUUACUUGCCAAAUAUAUAUUAAUACACAUACAAUUCUGACACCCCUCUGAACCUGAAGAAGAGUGUUGUCAAAGGAAAAAGAGGUCAAAAGUGGACCCUUGAGAUUUUCUAGCCCCAUUCCUGGUGUGAUUCUGUUACUUGUUCAAUAAAAGACGCUUUUCACAAAUGCUUAUUGAGAGCUCAAAUGUGUGCCAGGUAAAGAAGAUCUUGACUAGUUUGGGAGAACAAGGGGGGCCAGGGAAAACCAACAGAGUUAGGAGGCAUAUCCAGGCAGAGGGAAGAACACAUGCAGUGGCACAUGCGGAGAGAACAGGAUGUGUUGGAGGAACUCCAAGUAAUUAGAUAUGCCUGGAACAAAGAGGACAUCUGAGGAUUUGGAAGGAGCAGAGACUUAGCAAAGUGGGUGGAGGUCAUCACAUUCUGGCCCAGUCUGCCAAAGGACUUAAUAGCAAUUGUUUAAUUUUUUAAAGUUUUUCAGAUUUUAAGUCAGAUAAGAAUGCUAGUUCCUCUUGUAACAUACAGCUGGAUACCAAGGAAUUGAGGUUAAGAUGCAUAGUGUAUACAUCCAAACUACUAUAGCACAGUUCACUGAGAUGGACUUUUCCUUCCACUGAGCUCUGUACUGUGUUAGUUCCAUCAUAUUUAAACAUUGAUAAUAGUGACAGUAACCACACUUGUAAUGAUAAAAAUAAUGAGUUUGUCACUGGACCAUGCUUGCUUUAGAGCUUUGGUUUUUGUAAAAAUUUAACCUAUUAGGGGGAAAAAUGCUGUUUUACUGUUAACACAUGGCAAUCUGACCAGCACUUAGGACAGACUACUGCACAUCCACUGAGGGAAGCCCCUCAUGGUUUUGUUUGGGUUGAAUAAAAUCCUUCUCUUACUGUGGGGUUGGAGUCAUCUUAUUCCUCUGAGGUAUGUUAGCAGAUAAAGCAGAAUGGAGUAACUAAAGAGCUAAAGGACCCUCUUGUACCCCUUCCCUGAGCAUCUGGGAAAGACCCAUAUGGAAAUAUUAGACAGUGACUGGCUUUACUGAUGUUUUGAAGAUAGUCGGAUUCUGGUAGCUUAGCAUAUGUAAUGUGAACUUCAAGAUUUAUCCAAACGCUUAUUGCCAAUUACUACAGAAAGUUGGGUUGAUUACUCUUAUCGCUAAUCUUUGUAUCAAUAUAAAAUAAUAAGUAUUUGAUGAAAAUUUAAGUUACUUUUCACUUAGUCAAGAAUUUCUCAAACAGGGUCAUACUUUUUAGUCAUUUUAUAUCAUGAUAUCAUCUCAUUUCUCUCACCUUUUAUUUCAAGUGGAUAGGAAGAAACCAACCCAUUGGAAACUGAUUUUUUUUUUAAGACUUAAGGAGGAACUUGUACAACUUUCCUCUAUAAGUCAUUUUGCUAACAGUUUUUUCUUUAGUUUUUAGUUGUAGUAUUUUAAUUAUACAAUUAAUAUAUUGAUAAUGACUUAUUGUUAAAAAGUAAAAUGAUACAAGCCAGGCCUGGUGGCUCACGCCUGUAAUCCCAGCACUUUGGGAGGCCAAGGCAGGUGGAUCACCUGAGGUCAGGAGUUCGAAACCGGCUUGGCCAACAUGGUGAAACCUCAGCUCUACUAAAUAUACAAAAAUUGGCCGGGCGUGGUGGUGCACACCUGUAUUCUCAGCUACUCAGAAGGCUGAGGCGGGAGAAUCACUUGAAUGCAGGAGGCGGAGGUUGCAGUGAGCUGAGAUCGCACCACUGCACUCCAGCCUGGGCAAAGAAGUGAGACUCUAUCAAAAAAACAAACAACAACAACAACAACAAAAACUAAACUAAAACGAUAGAGACAUAUACAGAGUAAAAAGUUAGUCCCUCCCUUUUCCUUCUCCCCAUGCCCACUAUCCUCCUUGCCUCUCCAGCAGUAGUCACUGUUAACAGUUUGAUGUGUGGUCUCUGGCAUUUGCCUUAUGUGUAUACUAUAUGUACUUGUACAUACAUGCCUAGGCAAGUAGAUUGGAGUUGGUAAACAAUUUAUUUCUCUAAAUCAAAUCCCAGAAAGCAGAGUUUGUGCUUUAUGUUAUCUGAUUGCACUCUGAUUUUCUUUCUUACAGGAAAGCAUUCUUUAAGGCUUAGGAAACUAUAGGAAUUCUUUGAGGCUUUUCUUUUUUUACCUAGUUUAUUUAACUUAUUUUUAUUAGUAAUCUGAAUAAAGGUGCCAAAAUUUUAAAAUAUACUAAACCUGGAGGGAAAAAAUGUCUAUAUUUAGGAAUUUGGACUAAUCUUGUCAGCAUGUGAUGGUGAGGCUGAAAUGAAGAAAUAUUCAAUAGGGAUAAAAAUUUUAAAUUGCAUUUAAAAUUUUAAAAUGUGUUAUAGAAGUUUAGGAUGUAAGACUUGAUUUCAGCAGUAGUUAACUUGAAAAUAACCUGGUGAUGUUUGUUGGCAAGGACUAGCUGAUGUAGUGUCUGAAUGCAAUCUUAUGAUAACUGUAAUAGAAGUAUACUAUCCUGAUCAAGAAGGCACAAACCUCUUUGUACCCUUCCCUAAGCAGGCCACUUUCAGAAUACUAUAUUCAGGUACAGGAAAUAUAAGGUAAAACACAAGUAGCCCAGAGAUUUUAUUUCUGUUUGGAGCAAUAUGGAUACUAUCUAAGUGGGUUUGUAUAGCCCACUAAUUACUAAAUGCUUUGAAAUUAAUGGUUAUAUAAUAAGUAUAAACAAGUUUGAAUUUCAUCAGAUAGCUAGAUAAUGAAAUACUUGGUUGAUUUUUAGAAAGUAAGCAAGGACUUGGUAUUUUUGUAAUAGAAACACAUCAAAAAAUCAAUCCUUUAAUUAUAAUCUAAACCAAUUUCAAUAGCCUGUGCAUGGUCUCAUUGUUGCUACUCAAAAUGUGACCUUUAGCCCAGCAGCUUCAGUAUCACCUGGGAGCUUGUUAGAAAUGCAAACUCAAAGCUCAUCUAGACCAAUUGAAUGAGAACCUGUAAGUUAACAAGAUCCCCAGGUGACUUACGAACAUUAAAGUUUAAGAACCUGAAAAAUUCUGAACCCUCAACUGUGUUCAAUGAAAGCUUUAAAAAGUCCAUAAAGAUGGUGUCUCCAUACUUCUUGUGUAUCUUCUUGAAGCAUGAUGCAAUAGUUUGGUAAAGAAAUGAGAAAAGUAGAAGAUGAGGCAAUCGUGGUGGCUUAUUUGACUCUUGCAUUGUCCUUCUAGGCAAUACCAGUAUUCUUACCUUUUCACAUUUUUUAGUAUAGGUUGGAAUUAUUGAUAAGUAGUGAUAAUUCCUAGGAUGACUAAAUAGAAAAAUGUUUUAAGUUAUAGAAAAAAAUAAGAUCACUAAGAUCCCGUAAUGUAUCAUAGACUUAUAAAAGGGUUCAUUCUAUUCAUGUUAAUUGCAAGAGAGAAUAAAUUUGAUUCUACUUUAAAAAUAUAUAGGCAAUUUUUUUUCUGUGUUCUUUGGAAGAAAACUUCCAAAAAGAAAUUUAAAAAAUAAAAUUGGAUCCAGUUGACCCUGAGAAUUAACUGGGAGUUAAGAAUGUUAAGGCUCUUUCAAAACACACUGAAAACCAGAUCAUGUGUAUGAAAAUAUAACUAGGAAUGCGAAGUAUAUGAAAUGGAUAUCGUGAGUAUUGUAAAAGUUCAGAUGAAUGAGUAUUUGAUUAAUUCAUUCAAUAAAUAUUAAGUGCCCAUUAUGUGCCAGGCAUUGUUCUUGGAAUUGGGGCUAACUGGAGCUUAGAUUUUAGUGGAGGACCCAGCCAAUACACAAAUUAACAGGCCAGUGAAAGUCUGGGUAAUACGUGCUGUAAAGAAAAAAUAGAGCAGGUCAGGCGAUGGUGAAUGACUGCAGCACAGGCCAGGAUGCCACAAGCAGAUGCUUCCCUCUUCUUUGGUAACUAGGCCCUUGAGAUGAUGGGGAGAUAUGUAAGGAGUUACCAUUUGGCCAGACUCUGAAUAAAACACAAGAGCCAUGUGUGGGAAGUGGAGCAUAACCAAACUGCAGCAAUAGUUCUGUUUGUAAAGUCCUUUUAUCACCUUAAUUGAAUGGGACUGUCCUGUGGCCUCAGGGCUACCUAGGAUGCAAAUAAAAUCACCCACUAUUGGCUUUGUGGUAUCCUGAGAUACCACAGCACAAGAAAGGGGCUUGAGAUCCGCAGAGAUCAUUCUCCGCUAUCCAAGCUCUGAAACCCUUCAGUCUGAAGGCUGAAAAACACUGAUUCAUUGUAGUUCAAGUCUCACCUGAUAGCACCACUCUUGAGUCUGCAGUCUCAAUUUCCACAUCUGUAAAUUGGGAAAGAUACCCAACUUGCAAGGUUAUUGUGACAACCAUAAAGAGUAUGUAUCAGGUGCCUGACACGUACUAAGUGUUUAAUAAACAGUAACCAGUAUUACUCCCCAUGAGGGUUAGCUUAUUAACAUCUCAUUUCUAAGAUGUUAGAAAUGAUCCUCAGAUUCCUUAGAACCUAAGGUAGACAGUUUCAGCCUUAUGAUAUUACUAAGAUACAUAAUAACAAUUUAGAGUUCCCAUACAUAAAAGAUUGUUCUACCCAUUGCCUACCCUCACCCUCCAACUUAGCUCAUUACUCCCUCCAGAGAAUAGUAGUUGGGAGGUAGGGAUGAGAGUGGAUAGGCCCUGAAAAGGCAGUUUAGGGGUGUCAGUGUAAAAUGUGCACAGAUACAUAUUGUGUGAAGUCAGCUGCACGACAGCCAAAUAAUUUUAUGCAUUUUUAUGUAUCCACUCUUAUCCAUCCUGUAAACCUAGUUUCAUUCACAAAGGUGAACACAUUUAGUUUCUUCAAAUACAUGAGAGACUGGCUGGGAAUAAUCCCCCCAGGAGUUACCAAAAGAGGUUUCAACAUUUGAAGGCCACCCUGAGCCAUGGGAACAAUGGAGAGGACUCACUGUGUGACUCUAGUCUGUCUCCCUUGCCCCUGAGAGGAGAUAACACCUCCUCUUCUCUCAGUUCUGUACAGCUCAGCCUUGACCUUGAGGUUCCUGGGAAGUUGUUAGAAUUGUGUUAGGUUAGUACGAAAUCUAUUCAUUCCUAAGCUGAUCAGAUCCCAUUUCCUGACUUCUUGUCAUUGAAUACUUCACAUUUAGUUUACUCUGAAAUGUACGUUAAAAAAAGAAAAGACAAAGUCUUUUUGGAUGCUAUGUUUCAAACUGUGUGUUUUGUGAUCUUAAUGGUUUUUGCUAAUUUUAAAAAGCAGUGAGUUGGUGGUAGAAAAUAGCUGUUCUCAUCGAAUGUGUCUUUAAAAUGUUCUAUAAAACUAUCAACAAAACAGGGCAAACAUCAAGAUCUUGAAUCACUGGAUUUUUAUACAACACAAUGCCCAUGGUAGACAAAUACCAAAAACCAGAAAAUGCCUAAAACGUAAAUUUUAAAAAGGAAGGGAGAAGGGGAAGAAGGAAGAAGGAAAUAGAGGGGAAAAGGAAAUUAAAGGAAGAGAAGAAAGAAAGGAAAGAAUAAAAUGGAAUCAAGAGUCCUAUCCUUUAGAUACCAGAGAAAGCGCAGGCAGAAUUUUAUGGUGGGGUUCAUUUCUGCCUUGCUUCCUGCCUCAGCUUCUGUAGAAUGGCCCUUAAUCAUGGUGGCAGUGAUUCUGAUUGCAAGGCAGCCUUUGCUGAAGAAAAUCUGGCCAUCAGGGUUUUGAGGAUAAAGCAGUGAUCACAGACUUAAACCUUUAAGAGCCAACUGGGAAAUGCCCUCCCAUUUGAGAUGCCCUGGUUUGUGCUGACCUCCAACUGAUAGAGUUAGGGAUGGGUGGAAGUCCCAGUCAGCAUCAGGGUGGCAAAAAGUGCCCAAGAAGUGUGUCCUUCUUGGCUCUUCUGUUUCCCACCUACCCACAGAAGGCAGGCAUGCAUGGUGAGCCAGUCUACCAGCACUAGGAGCUGCACAUUCCAUGCCAAGAAGACCCUCUCAGAUUUCUAUAAGAAGUCAGUCCUGUGAGACUGCCUUACAUGGAUCCCUACUACCUCCAAGUGGUGUAUUUAUUGCCAAUAGAAGGGACAGGUCCAGGGCAUCCCUGGAUAUUAGGCCACACUGAUUCCUGGUGGUGGCGAUGGACGGGGCAUUAGAGGUGGUGCUGGUGCUGCUGGCUGUAACAGUGGUGUGAUGAGGUAGGGGAGGCUGGCUUGCUCUGGGGUGCUCAGAAUAUGGCUCUUCAAUUACAUAGAUCCAUUUUUGGUUGUCUUGAGUCUUUUCUGCACAUUUUACUUUCCAUAUGGAGUCAUUUCCCUUUGGCAUGAAGAGCAUCUUUAGCAUACUAUGUAGUGCAGUUCUGCUGGUUACAGAUUCUCUCACUUGGGCAUAUAUGAAUAUGUCCUUAUUUAGCCCUCAUUUUUGAAGGCUAUUCUGGUCUCUUCUUCUGCAGUCCCCAGCCAACCACUGAUCUCCUCUCUGUCACUAUAAGUUAUAUUUUCUAGAAUUUCAUAUAAAUGGAAACAUACAGUAUGUAAUUUUUGUGUAGCUUUUUUCAUGCAGAAUAAUUUUGAGAUACAUCCAUGUUGUGUGUACAUCAAUUGUUCAUUCCUUUAUAUUGCUGAGUAGUAUUUACUAUAUGGCUAUACACAAUUUGUCACCUGUUGAUGGACAUUUGGGAGUUUCUGCUUUUUAGCAAUUACAAAUAAAAUUGCUAUGAAUAUUUGCGUUCAAGUCUUUGCAUGGGGGUGGAAAACCUUUAUUCAAAUUACUAAUAAAAAUAAGUUAAAUAAACUAGGUAAAAAAAGAAAAGCCUCAAAGAAUUCCUAUAGUUUCCUAAGCCUUAAAGAAUGCUUUCCUGUAAGAAAGAAAAUCAGAGUGCAAUCAGAUAACAUAAACACAAACUCUGCUUUCUGGGAUUUGAUUUAGAGAAAUAAAUUGUUUACCAACUCCAAUCUACUUGCCUAGGCAUGUAUGUACAAGUACAUAUAGUAUACACAUAAGGCAAAUGCCAGAGACCACACAUCAAACUGUUAACAGUGACUACUGCUGGAGAGGCAAGGAGGAUAGUGGGCAUGGGGAGAAGGAAAAGGGAGGGACUAACUUUUUACUCUGUAUAUGUCUCUAUCGUUUUAGUUUAGUUUUUGUUGUUGUUGUUGUUGUUUGUUUUUUUGAUAGAGUCUCACUUCUUUGCCCAGGCUGGAGUGCAGUGGUGCGAUCUCAGCUCACUGCAACCUCCGCCUCCUGCAUUCAAGUGAUUCUCCCGCCUCAGCCUUCUGAGUAGCUGAGAAUACAGGUGUGCACCACCACGCCCGGCCAAUUUUUGUAUAUUUAGUAGAGCUGAGGUUUCACCAUGUUGGCCAAACCGGUUUCGAACUCCUCUUUUCUCUUGGAUGGAUACCUGGGGGUGGAAAACUGGAUCAUAUGGUAGGUGUAUGUUUAUGUUUUUACCAAACUACUGAACUGUUUUGCAAAGUGGUUGUACCAUUUUACAUUCCUACCAACUGUGGUAAGUAAUCAGGGGUCCAGAGUUAAAUAAGGCUCUCCCUGCUACCAGUCUUUCCAUUCUUCUCAUAUUUGCUGUACACAGCCACAAAUUGAAUUCCAAGUCAUUGAACACAGACUUUCUUGUAAGGGCAAGGAGUUGUUCUGGAAGUGGAUCUAGGGUUAUUUCGCAGAGAAUUCUGUGGCCUGGGGAACUUGAAAUGUCAUCUGGGGAGGCUAAGUUGUGGCCAUAGGGAGGCAUGAUCCCUUGGCUCAAAGGAUUUUUUUUUUUUUUUUGCUUUGUGGAGGGACGUGGCCAAAGGAUGACCAGAAGGGGGCCUUGAAAGUGUGGGGCUCAGGCCAGUGCCUCUCGCUCAGGUCUAAGGGCUAUACUGUUCCCUUCUCAUCCACCCAAUUCUAACCAUCUUGAAAAACCCAUCCUGCAUCCGCACGCCUGUAUCUUCUGUCGUGUGGCAGUUCUGUGUGUCCUCCUCCUCUCGGUUGUUUGCUGUUUGACUUUCUAUGUCUCACUUUCCCAAUUUGUGCAUAAACUUUUCAGUCAACUACUCUGUCUCCUUUUCCUUCAUAUGUAUGACAAAGUGUUAUGUACACGAAUGCUGUUCAAAAAUGUGUCAAUGAAAUGCAUGGAGUUUGCUGCUUUUUCUCUGCUCCUAAGUUGGUGUUAAUCUUCAGACAUUGUCCAGCACACUUGACAUUUACAUACAGAAUCUAGUCUAGUGUGCAGCUAGGACUUUGUGGUCCAAGCUCUGCCCAGUUAGCCUUCCUAAUCUCACCCCAGUUCACUAACACUGCAGACCUCUCUGUGCUUAUGCUAUGUUUUACUAUUCCAGUGUAAACCUCAGUUUGUUCCCCUGACAUCACCUCAUCUCAUCAUUGCCUUUUUAGACUACUUCCUUACUAACUAUAUUAAGUAACCCAGAAAUAAAGAGAGAAUUUUUAUCAGGUUUCUGAUUUUCCCAGCAUUGGCUGUGGUUCUCUCUGUCAGAUAGGUCACUAGAGACCCUGGCCAUAAAAACAUUUCCCAAGGGAGUCAUGCCUCAAUGUGUUUUAUCUAUGUUAAUCUUUCUUUCUGAUGUGUUCUUUCUUUCCUUCUCCAUCUGGAAAAUGUCUCCAGUCUUUCAAAAUUCAGCCACAGCAUUAUCUCUUCCAAGAAGGCUUUACUUUUUAAGAGAUCUAAAUUAAAGUAUGUUUCUCUAUCCUUUAUAGCACAUCUCUUAUAAUAUUUAAGACACUGGUACUGCAAUUUUUUUAUUUAUUUGUGUAUUACUCUCUCUCCACUAAGAACUCUGUGACGAUAAGGACCACAUCUCAUUUGACUUUAUUUUUCAGCAUAUAACAGUGCUAGUAUAUAAAAUCCUCAAAUAAUUGGUUAAUGAAUCAAUAAAUUAAUGAAUAAAGGAAUGGAAUGCCUCUUUUUAUUCAUCUCUUUCCUUUUCUGUUCUCCACAUCUUCCCUUGUUUUACUUUUGUUUCUGCCCUUCUUCCACUGUGACUAAAUUUUUGCAAUAUAGAAAUAAUACGGGCUUUGUGACCUUUAGCGUUUUCUUAGCUCUACAAAUGUUGGAAAAUGGAUUUUGAACCUUAGCAAACAAGCUGAAACAGUUUAAACAUUUGUUUGUGGGUGCAGCAAUGGAAGAAAGACUUCAUUGGCAUUUGUUAUGAUGGUGAGUACAUUUGUGAGAUUAACAUUCUUUGCUCAAGACUGAGAGGCCUCUGGUCAGCCGCCCCCAUUCUAAAGCAACACAGAUCAUAUUCUGUCACACUGAGAUCUCAGGUAACUGACCUUUCUCACAUCGGGGGCCUCCCGAGAUGCCCUACAUGGAAACAAAGAUGAAUAUACUGUUUAAAAAUUUUCAGGCUUGGUUUAGCCCAGAUAUUUUUUAUAAAGAUAUUAUGAAAUAAUGAAGAUAAAGUUCCUUAUAUGCUGGCCAGCAAUAGUAGGUGCCAGUCAAUGUUAGUCAUCAUCUUCAUCCUCUUUCCCAAGCUUUCUAAAGUUCCCGAAGACAUACGUUUCCUUGAAAUUUCUCUCAGGAUCAGAGUCACAAAUAAGGAAUAGGUCCAAGUGAUAUGUGCCAGGCAGCAAACAUGCCGCUCCUCUUUUUCAGAUGCCAGCAAAUUAAUCAUCUGUUUUGGCACUUACAACUUUUUUUGAGAGUGAGCUGAAUCUAAUGCAUGCUCCAUAUCAACUUCCCGAGGCUGUCAUGCUCAGCUCACACACAGUCAGGGACCAACCCGCUGGCCCCACCUUCCUGGAAAUACUGGAACAUCUAAAGGCCUUUGAUGAUGAAAUCAAUGCUUUUUUGGACAAUAUGUUUGGACCGCGAGAUUCUCGAGUCAGAGGGUGGUUCAUGUUGGACUCUUACCUUCCUACCUUUUUUCUUACUGUCAUGUAUCUGCUCUCAAUAUGGCUGGGUAACAAGUAUAUGAAGAACAGACCUGCUCUUUCUCUCAGGGGUAUCCUCACCUUGUAUAAUCUUGGAAUCACACUUCUCUCCGCGUACAUGCUGGCAGAGCUCAUUCUCUCCACUUGGGAAGGAGGCUACAACUUACAGUGUCAAGAUCUUACCAGCGCAGGGGAAGCUGACAUCCGGGUAGCCAAGGUGCUUUGGUGGUACUAUUUCUCCAAAUCAGUAGAGUUCCUGGACACAAUUUUCUUCGUUUUGCGGAAAAAAACGAGUCAGAUUACUUUUCUUCAUGUAUAUCAUCAUGCUUCUAUGUUUAACAUCUGGUGGUGUGUCUUGAACUGGAUACCUUGUGGACAAAGUUUCUUUGGACCAACACUGAACAGUUUUAUCCACAUUCUUAUGUACUCCUACUAUGGACUUUCUGUGUUUCCAUCUAUGCACAAGUAUCUUUGGUGGAAGAAAUAUCUCACACAGGCUCAGCUGGUGCAGUUCGUGCUCACCAUCACGCACACCAUGAGCGCCGUCGUGAAACCGUGUGGCUUCCCCUUCGGUUGUCUCAUCUUCCAGUCAUCUUAUAUGCUAACGUUAGUCAUCCUCUUCUUAAAUUUUUACGUUCAGACAUACCGAAAAAAGCCAAUGAAGAAAGAUAUGCAAGAGCCACCUGCAGGGAAAGAAGUGAAGAAUGGUUUUUCCAAAGCCUACUUCACUGCAGCAAAUGGAGUGAUGAACAAGAAAGCACAAUAAAAAUGAGUAACAGAAAAAGCACAUAUACUAGCCUAACAGAUUGGCUUGUUUUAAAGCAAAGACUGAAUUGAAGGUUACAUGUUUUAGGAUAAACUAAUUUCUUUUGAGUUCAUAAAUCAUUUGUACCCAGAAUGUAUUAAUAUAUUGCUAUUAGGUUAAUCUGUUAACUGAAUGCUUUGAUCAGCAUUGAGGUGAUGCUCACCUCCGAGGACCUCAGAACUGGUGCAGCUUCUCUCUCCCUCCCUCCCACAGACUGAACCUUUCGCCAGAAGCUGUCCUUAUAACGCCUUAUACGCAUACACAGCCAGGAAACGUGGAGCAUUGUUUCUCACAGAGAGUCUCCAAAUAAAAAGGGUUUUGUUCAGAUUAAAAUGUUUACAACAAAAUGUUAAUUAUAUUCUAAAUACAGGGUAUGUUCUAAUCUAUAUUAAGCAAUAAUGCCAGUGCAUAAUCAUUCCAUUUGUUCCUUUAGCAAUCAACCCCAGAAAAUAUUAAAAUGGGAUCAUACACAGAAGAUAGAAAAAUCUAGCAAAACUUCUCUUUCUGUAAGCCAGAGUCUUGUCUAUCAGAUUCCCACAACCACUCCUGAUUCUAAAUUUAGUGAUAUGGUAAUGAAAUUGGUAUUUAUUUUAAAUAUUAGUUAUUCUAAGGAGAAAAAAAUGCUUCUGCAAGAUUUUCAUAAUUCAGGGGCUGUGGAUAGGAUUGUUCCUCUGUUUCCCUAAUCAUUCAUCUGUUCAUGUCUCCCUCUUGUGCCAGUCAGCCUAGGUUAUACAGAUGCCAUGCUCCACACCACGAGCAGUGUACAAAUCUGGCUGCCCGUUUACUUUCUGAGCAAGCACUGGAGUCCACUCCGACCUUUUUCUUUGAACAUGCAUGCUGCUGGAAUAUGUAUAAAUCAGAACUAGCAGAAGUAGCAGAGUGAUGGGAGCAAAAUAGGCACUGAAUUCGUCAACUCUUUUUUGUGAGCCUACUUGUGAAUAUUACCUCAGAUACCUGUUGUCACUCUUCACAGGUUAUUUAAGUUUUUGAAGCUGGGAGGAAAAAGAUGGAGUAGCUUGGAAAGAUUCCAGCACUGAGCCGUGGGCCGGUCAUGAGCCACGAUAAAAAAUGCCAGUUUGGCAAACUCAGCACUCCUGUUCCCUGCUCAGGUAUAUGCGAUCUCUACCGAGAAGCAAGCACAAAAGUAGACAAAAGUAUUAAUGAGUAUUUCCUUUCUCCAUAAGUGCAGGACUGUUACUCACUACUAAACUCUACCAAGAAUGGAAACAAAGAAUAUUUUCUGAAGAUUUUUUUGAAGAUUAAUUUAUACCCUAUAAAAUAAAACUUGUUAGCUUCGAUGAAGUCACUUCAUCUUCUCUCCUGCCUUAUUUUUUUAAAUAAGUUUUUAGGUCCUGACACUGACAUCAAAUACAUGCACACCAGAAAGGCAUUUCCACCACCGUCCCCACUCAUUAGCGUCCAGAGUGCCUUUCUCUCUCGGCUUUUUUUCCCCCCUGAGCUCUAGUUUUAAACUUUCUCCUGUUAAAAAAAUUGUACUUUUAUUUCAUGUAAACUGCCCCUCUGAGGAUUUGGGCAUAUUUUUUGGAAGGUGCCUAAUGCUUAGGAUAGUCUCUAGGGUGAUGCACUGCACCUGCUUCCUUCCCUUCAGUGCGGCCGACCCAUUUCUGUUGAACAGAUGUCUCCUGUGUGAUGCCCCUGACUCUUACAUUUAUCUUUCUAAAUCAUUUUCUGAAGCUGACUUGCUCUAGGGUGCUUCAUCACCACUUCCAUCUUGCAUCACCUUAUAACUGUUCUGUCUUGUUCUCUCCCAGCAAUUUAUUUUAAAACAAGGGCUAGCUUCAAGCAUGACUGUUAAUGGCUCCUCUGUGACAAAACACAAGUUGGACCAAGGAGAAAGCCCUUUGGAGAAACUGGACCCUAGUUCAGUUUAGAUCUCAAAUAUAGGCUGAAAUCUCUUACCAAAGUGCGUUCCAGAUAAAAAUGAGACUUAGAAGACAGACUGGUCUAAUAUGCUCACUGGUCAUCACAUUCAGCUUAUUCUUACGUGCCAGUGAGGCCCUAAGGUCUCAGUGCAUAGCAUACCUGCCACUCUGGAUGUUUUCCUGGGCUUCAUAUCUGUAUGGCAAGGAGGGAGCUGUCCUUCAGCAGACAAAGUCAAGCAGCUUUAAGUACAAGGCAGCUUGAAACCUCUCUGAUGAAAGUGAAAAAUGUGGGUAGCUUAUACUUUCAAACUAAUGCCAGUGACUAGAGAGAGGUUUCAUUCAUGAUGUGUAUUUCCAAUUUGGUCUUCAAUUCAAGAGAUGCUUCAUAAAACACUUAUAGCCUUAAACCAUUCAAGGGCUAAUUAAAAAAAUAGUUAUGAAAUCUUAGCCACAAAAAAUAAAUCAGGUAAACAUUUUAACCUGUCGUUAAGUGUUGUAACUUCAAAAAACCAAAAUGCUUAUUUUAAUGUGAUUUUUCUAAAACUAUUGAAAAAUUAAUAUUUCUAUAAUCUAUUAAAAAAAAUGGAGAAUGUUUUCUCUCAAAUUUCCUCUGACCCAUGGGAAUGAAAAUACUUAAAUACUGUAAAGCAUAUCUAUUAAUAAUUCCCCCAAUUUUUUAAACUAACAAAAUGGAAUGUUAACUGAAUGGAAUUAAACAUAGCAAUUGUCAAGCCAUCAAAAUUAUAUAUCGAACCACUUAGGCAUGUUACGGGGUAAAGUCCUCACCCCUGCAUUUGAGAAAUAUUUUAUUAUUUUUAUUUUAAGGCAAAACAGUGUUUACUGUGAUGGGCAGAACAGCCUUUUGUAUCUAGGAGUCCAUUUGAGUUCUUUCCAAUAUUUCCAUAUCGUUCAUAAAUGUGUCUGGGGGCUUCCUUGUUUGGAAAAUAUGGAUAUCGCUUUGUUUUCCUUUGAAAGUAAUUAUAUCUUAAGAACAUAGUAUCAUGAAUGGAGUAGACAGGGAGGCUGCAGAAGCCAUUUCUCUUUGUAGAUAAAAAGCAUUAUCUAUGAUUGUUGUAUAAUAAAUUGAUUUUUACAUUAAA